GUAACUUCCGGUGUACACAGCCGGUCCAAGGCGGUGCGCUGGGGGCCGGGGCGCGUCGCAGGAAAGGACUUAGAAGCCUUACAAAUACAUCUGUGCAUUCUUGCUUCAGACUUUACAACUGAGGGCCAGCCCAGUCUGGAAGCAUCUCUUAUUAAUGUUACAAGGAAACCGCUACCUCAGCAAACAAAAGGAAUGGAGGAGGAGACUUACAACAAACGCCAUUUAAAAAAAAAAGAAAAACUUGUUUUCAGGAAACAUUAGAGGAAAUUUGGAGAAUUUCAGCAUUGCAUAGAAGCAGCCUUACAGGUAAACGGAUUUGACGGGCAGGCUCUGUCAAAAUUCUGCAGAAGUUUGAUCUUCCUUCUUAAGGACUUUGUGUGAAGUAAUUCUUUACUGCUUUUAAAUUGCUGUUGAUCAGCUUCUGGGUUUUUGGGUUCUAACUUUUUUGGGUAUAUUGAAGACACAGUGUAUUACAUUAUAUUACAUUUUUAAACGUUAAGUUAUUUUUCUGCCAUUGUAAAUACAAGUAUCAAAAUAUUCUUGCAAAGAAGUAAACAUUUUUCUCAGCAAGCAUAUCCUUUUAGUAAGAGAGUGGAAUGCUAAACAGUUCUUAUCCAGCAUUUUGGACAUCUUUUAUUUUUUGUCAGAGAUCCUGUCUACACUGAAAAUAUUAAUUAUAUAAACCUGUUGUCUCUCACCUCUACAUUGGAUCACAUGGUCACCUGCCUCAUGGAAAUGCCUUUUUUAAAACUUCGAUUUGCAGAACUCCACUAUUUUUAUACCUAGCUACAGUUUUGAGAAAGAAGAAUCAGAACCCUGACCCACUUACGGUUGCUGGGACAAUUCCCCCUCCCGCAUGUAUUGCUGCAGUGCCCAGGACAGUAAAAUGGACUACAAGCGGCGCUUCCUGCUUGGCGGGUCCAAGCAGAAGGUGCAGCAGCACCAGCAAUACCCGAUGCCUGAGCUGGGCCGAGCACUGAGUGCUCCCCUGGCAUCCACGGCCACCACUGCCCCCCUGGGCAGUCUGACCGCUGCAGGCAGCUGCCACCAUGCCAUGCCCCACACUACUCCUAUCGCCGACAUCCAGCAGGGCAUCUCCAAGUAUCUGGAUGCCCUGAACGUCUUCUGCCGUGCCAGUACUUUCCUCACAGAUCUCUUCAGCACUGUGUUCAGGAACUCUCACUACUCAAAGGCAGCCACACAGCUCAAAGAUGUGCAGGAGCAUGUCAUGGAAGCAGCCAGUCGGCUGACCUCGGCCAUAAAGCCUGAGAUCGCCAAGAUGCUAAUGGAACUUAGUGCUGGGGCUGCAAAUUUUACGGAUCAGAAGGAAUUC